ACACUCUGGGCGCGGAGCACAAUGAUUGGUCACUCCUAUUUUCGCUGAGCUUUUCCUCUUAUUUCAGUUUUCUUCGAGAUCAAAUCUGGUUUGUAGAUGUGCUUGGGGAGAAUGGGGGCCUCUUCUCCAAGAAGCCCGGAGCCUGUCGGGCCGCCGGCGCCCGGUCUCCCCUUCUGCUGCGGAGGAUCCCUGCUGGCGGUUGUGGUGCUGCUUGCGCUGCCGGUGGCCUGGGGUCAAUGCAAUGCCCCAGAAUGGCUUCCAUUUGCCAGGCCUACCAACCUAACUGAUGAAUUUGAGUUUCCCAUUGGGACAUAUCUGAACUAUGAAUGCCGCCCUGGUUAUUCCGGAAGACCGUUUUCUAUCAUCUGCCUAAAAAACUCAGUCUGGACUGGUGCUAAGGACAGGUGCAGACGUAAAUCAUGUCGUAAUCCUCCAGAUCCUGUGAAUGGCAUGGUGCAUGUGAUCAAAGGCAUCCAGUUCGGAUCCCAAAUUAAAUAUUCUUGUACUAAAGGAUACCGACUCAUUGGUUCCUCGUCUGCCACAUGCAUCAUCUCAGGUGAUACUGUCAUUUGGGAUAAUGAAACACCUAUUUGUGACAGAAUUCCUUGUGGGCUACCCCCCACCAUCACCAAUGGAGAUUUCAUUAGCACCAACAGAGAGAAUUUUCACUAUGGAUCAGUGGUGACCUACCGCUGCAAUCCUGGAAGCGGAGGGAGAAAGGUGUUUGAGCUUGUGGGUGAGCCCUCCAUAUACUGCACCAGCAAUGACGAUCAAGUGGGCAUCUGGAGCGGCCCCGCCCCUCAGUGCAUUAUACCUAACAAAUGCACGCCUCCAAAUGUGGAAAAUGGAAUAUUGGUAUCUGACAACAGAAGCUUAUUUUCCUUAAAUGAAGUUGUGGAGUUUAGGUGUCAGCCUGGCUUUGUCAUGAAAGGACCCCGCCGUGUGAAGUGCCAGGCCCUGAACAAAUGGGAGCCGGAGCUACCAAGCUGCUCCAGGGUAUGUCAGCCACCUCCAGAUGUCCUGCAUGCUGAGCGUACCCAAAGGGACAAGGACAACUUUUCACCUGGGCAGGAAGUGUUCUACAGCUGUGAGCCCGGCUACGACCUCAGAGGGGCUGCGUCUAUGCGCUGCACACCCCAGGGAGACUGGAGCCCUGCAGCCCCCACAUGUGAAGUGAAAUCCUGUGAUGACUUCAUGGGCCAACUUCUUAAUGGCCGUGUGCUAUUUCCAGUAAAUCUCCAGCUUGGAGCAAAAGUGGAUUUUGUUUGUGAUGAAGGAUUUCAAUUAAAAGGCAGCUCUGCUAGUUACUGUGUCUUGGCUGGAAUGGAAAGCCUUUGGAAUAGCAGUGUUCCAGUGUGUGAACAAAUCUUUUGUCCAAGUCCUCCAGUUAUUCCUAAUGGGAGACACACAGGAAAACCUCUGGAAGUCUUUCCCUUUGGGAAAACAGUAAAUUACACAUGCGACCCCCACCCAGACAGAGGGACGAGCUUCGACCUCAUUGGAGAGAGCACCAUCCGCUGCACAAGUGACCCUCAAGGGAAUGGGGUUUGGAGCAGCCCUGCCCCUCGCUGUGGAAUUCUGGGUCACUGUCAAGCCCCAGAUCAUUUUCUGUUUGCCAAGUUGAAAACCCAAACCAAUGCAUCUGACUUUCCCAUUGGGACAUCUUUAAAGUACGAAUGCCGUCCUGAGUACUACGGGAGGCCAUUCUCUAUCACAUGUCUAGAUAACCUGGUCUGGUCAAGUCCCAAAGAUGUCUGUAAACGUAAAUCAUGUAAAACUCCUCCAGAUCCAGUGAAUGGCAUGGUGCAUGUGAUCACAGACAUCCAGGUUGGAUCCAGAAUCAACUAUUCUUGUACUACAGGGCACCGACUCAUUGGUCACUCAUCUGCUGAAUGUAUCCUCUCGGGCAAUGCUGCCCAUUGGAGCACGAAGCCGCCAAUUUGUCAACGAAUUCCUUGUGGGCUACCCCCCACCAUCGCCAAUGGAGAUUUCAUUAGCACCAACAGAGAGAAUUUUCACUAUGGAUCAGUGGUGACCUACCGCUGCAAUCCUGGAAGCGGAGGGAGAAAGGUGUUUGAGCUUGUGGGUGAGCCCUCCAUAUACUGCACCAGCAAUGACGAUCAAGUGGGCAUCUGGAGCGGCCCGGCCCCUCAGUGCAUUAUACCUAACAAAUGCACGCCUCCAAAUGUGGAAAAUGGAAUAUUGGUAUCUGACAACAGAAGCUUAUUUUCCUUAAAUGAAGUUGUGGAGUUUAGGUGUCAGCCUGGCUUUGUCAUGAAAGGACCCCGCCGUGUGAAGUGCCAGGCCCUGAACAAAUGGGAGCCGGAGCUACCAAGCUGCUCCAGGGUAUGUCAGCCACCUCCAGAUGUCCUGCAUGCUGAGCGUACCCAAAGGGACAAGGACAACUUUUCACCCGGGCAGGAAGUGUUCUACAGCUGUGAGCCCGGCUACGACCUCAGAGGGGCUGCGUCUAUGCGCUGCACACCCCAGGGAGACUGGAGCCCUGCAGCCCCCACAUGUGAAGUGAAAUCCUGUGAUGACUUCAUGGGCCAACUUCUUAAUGGCCGUGUGCUAUUUCCAGUAAAUCUCCAGCUUGGAGCAAAAGUGGAUUUUGUUUGUGAUGAAGGAUUUCAAUUAAAAGGCAGCUCUGCUAGUUACUGUGUCUUGGCUGGAAUGGAAAGCCUUUGGAAUAGCAGUGUUCCAGUGUGUGAACAAAUCUUUUGUCCAAGUCCUCCAGUUAUUCCUAAUGGGAGACACACAGGAAAACCUCUGGAAGUCUUUCCCUUUGGGAAAACAGUAAAUUACACAUGCGACCCCCACCCAGACAGAGGGACGAGCUUCGACCUCAUUGGAGAGAGCACCAUCCGCUGCACAAGUGACCCUCAAGGGAAUGGGGUUUGGAGCAGCCCUGCCCCUCGCUGUGGAAUUCUGGGUCACUGUCAAGCCCCAGAUCAUUUUCUGUUUGCCAAGUUGAAAACCCAAACCAAUGCAUCUGACUUUCCCAUUGGGACAUCUUUAAAGUACGAAUGCCGUCCUGAGUACUACGGGAGGCCAUUCUCUAUCACAUGUCUAGAUAACCUGGUCUGGUCAAGUCCCAAAGAUGUCUGUAAACGUAAAUCAUGUAAAACUCCUCCAGAUCCAGUGAAUGGCAUGGUGCAUGUGAUCACAGACAUCCAGGUUGGAUCCAGAAUCAACUAUUCUUGUACUACAGGGCACCGACUCAUUGGUCACUCAUCUGCUGAAUGUAUCCUCUCGGGCAAUGCUGCCCAUUGGAGCACGAAGCCGCCAAUUUGUCAACGAAUUCCUUGUGGGCUACCCCCCACCAUCGCCAAUGGAGAUUUCAUUAGCACCAACAGAGAGAAUUUUCACUAUGGAUCAGUGGUGACCUACCGCUGCAAUCCUGGAAGCGGAGGGAGAAAGGUGUUUGAGCUUGUGGGUGAGCCCUCCAUAUACUGCACCAGCAAUGACGAUCAAGUGGGCAUCUGGAGCGGCCCGGCCCCUCAGUGCAUUAUACCUAACAAAUGCACGCCUCCAAAUGUGGAAAAUGGAAUAUUGGUAUCUGACAACAGAAGCUUAUUUUCCUUAAAUGAAGUUGUGGAGUUUAGGUGUCAGCCUGGCUUUGUCAUGAAAGGACCCCGCCGUGUGAAGUGCCAGGCCCUGAACAAAUGGGAGCCGGAGCUACCAAGCUGCUCCAGGGUAUGUCAGCCACCUCCAGAUGUCCUGCAUGCUGAGCGUACCCAAAGGGACAAGGACAACUUUUCACCCGGGCAGGAAGUGUUCUACAGCUGUGAGCCCGGCUAUGACCUCAGAGGGGCUGCGUCUAUGCGCUGCACACCCCAGGGAGACUGGAGCCCUGCAGCCCCCACAUGUGAAGUGAAAUCCUGUGAUGACUUCAUGGGCCAACUUCUUAAUGGCCGUGUGCUAUUUCCAGUAAAUCUCCAGCUUGGAGCAAAAGUGGAUUUUGUUUGUGAUGAAGGAUUUCAAUUAAAAGGCAGCUCUGCUAGUUAUUGUGUCUUGGCUGGAAUGGAAAGCCUUUGGAAUAGCAGUGUUCCAGUGUGUGAACAAAUCUUUUGUCCAAGUCCUCCAGUUAUUCCUAAUGGGAGACACACAGGAAAACCUCUGGAAGUCUUUCCCUUUGGAAAAGCAGUAAAUUACACAUGCGACCCCCACCCAGACAGAGGGACGAGCUUCGACCUCAUUGGAGAGAGCACCAUCCGCUGCACAAGUGACCCUCAAGGGAAUGGGGUUUGGAGCAGCCCUGCCCCUCGCUGUGGAAUUCUGGGUCACUGUCAAGCCCCAGAUCAUUUUCUGUUUGCCAAGUUGAAAACCCAAACCAAUGCAUCUGACUUUCCCAUUGGGACAUCUUUAAAGUACGAAUGCCGUCCUGAGUACUACGGGAGGCCAUUCUCUAUCACAUGUCUAGAUAACCUGGUCUGGUCAAGUCCCAAAGAUGUCUGUAAACGUAAAUCAUGUAAAACUCCUCCAGAUCCAGUGAAUGGCAUGGUGCAUGUGAUCACAGACAUCCAGGUUGGAUCCAGAAUCAACUAUUCUUGUACUACAGGGCACCGACUCAUUGGUCACUCAUCUGCUGAAUGUAUCCUCUCAGGCAAUACUGCCCAUUGGAGCACGAAGCCGCCAAUUUGUCAACGAAUUCCUUGUGGGCUACCCCCAACCAUCGCCAAUGGAGAUUUCAUUAGCACCAACAGAGAGAAUUUUCACUAUGGAUCAGUGGUGACCUACCGCUGCAAUCUUGGAAGCAGAGGGAGAAAGGUGUUUGAGCUUGUGGGUGAGCCCUCCAUAUACUGCACCAGCAAUGACGAUCAAGUGGGCAUCUGGAGCGGCCCCGCCCCUCAGUGCAUUAUACCUAACAAAUGCACGCCUCCAAAUGUGGAAAAUGGAAUAUUGGUAUCUGACAACAGAAGCUUAUUUUCCUUAAAUGAAGUUGUGGAGUUUAGGUGUCAGCCUGGCUUUGUCAUGAAAGGACCCCGCCGUGUGAAGUGCCAGGCCCUGAACAAAUGGGAGCCAGAGUUACCAAGCUGCUCCAGGGUGUGUCAGCCGCCUCCAGAAAUCCUGCAUGGUGAGCAUACCCCAAGCCAUCAGGACAACUUUUCACCUGGGCAGGAAGUGUUCUACAGCUGUGAGCCUGGCUAUGACCUCAGAGGGGCUGCGUCUCUGCACUGCACACCCCAGGGAGACUGGAGCCCUGAAGCCCCGAGAUGUGCAGUGAAAUCCUGUGAUGACUUCUUGGGUCAACUCCCUCAUGGCCGUGUGCUAUUUCCACUUAAUCUCCAGCUUGGGGCAAAGGUGUCCUUUGUCUGUGAUGAAGGGUUUCGCUUAAAGGGCAGUUCCGUUAGUCAUUGUGUCUUGGUUGGAAUGAGAAGCCUUUGGAAUAACAGUGUUCCUGUGUGUGAACAUAUCUUUUGUCCAAAUCCUCCAGCUAUCCUUAAUGGGAGACACACAGGAACUCCCUCUGGAGAUAUUCCCUAUGGAAAAGAAAUAUCUUACACAUGUGACCCCCACCCAGACAGAGGGAUGACCUUCAACCUCAUUGGGGAGAGCACCAUCCGCUGCACAAGUGACCCUCAUGGGAAUGGGGUUUGGAGCAGCCCUGCCCCUCGCUGUGAACUUUCUGUUCGUGCUGGUCACUGUAAAACCCCAGAGCAGUUUCCAUUUGCCAGUCCUACGAUCCCAAUUAAUGACUUUGAGUUUCCAGUCGGGACAUCUUUGAAUUAUGAAUGCCGUCCUGGGUAUUUUGGGAAAAUGUUCUCUAUCUCCUGCCUAGAAAACUUGGUCUGGUCAAGUGUUGAAGACAACUGUAGACGAAAAUCAUGUGGACCUCCACCAGAACCCUUCAAUGGAAUGGUGCAUAUAAACACAGAUACACAGUUUGGAUCAACAGUUAAUUAUUCUUGUAAUGAAGGGUUUCGACUCAUUGGUUCCCCAUCUACUACUUGUCUCGUCUCAGGCAAUAAUGUCACAUGGGAUAAGAAGGCACCUAUUUGUGAGAUCAUAUCUUGUGAGCCACCUCCAACCAUAUCCAAUGGAGACUUCUACAGCAACAAUAGAACAUCUUUUCACAAUGGAACGGUGGUAACUUACCAGUGCCACACUGGACCAGAUGGAGAACAGCUGUUUGAGCUUGUGGGAGAACGGUCAAUAUAUUGCACCAGCAAAGAUGAUCAAGUUGGUGUUUGGAGCAGCCCUCCCCCUCGGUGUAUUUCUACUAAUAAAUGCACAGCUCCAGAAGUUGAAAAUGCAAUUAGAGUACCAGGAAACAGGAGUUUCUUUACCCUCACUGAGAUCAUCAGAUUUAGAUGUCAGCCCGGGUUUGUCAUGGUAGGGUCCCACACUGUGCAGUGCCAGACCAAUGGCAGAUGGGGGCCCAAGCUGCCACACUGCUCCAGGGUGUGUCAGCCGCCUCCAGAAAUCCUGCAUGGUGAGCAUACCCUAAGCCAUCAGGACAACUUUUCACCUGGGCAGGAAGUGUUCUACAGCUGUGAGCCCAGCUAUGACCUCAGAGGGGCUGCGUCUCUGCACUGCACGCCCCAGGGAGACUGGAGCCCUGAAGCCCCUAGAUGUACAGUGAAAUCCUGUGAUGACUUCCUGGGCCAACUCCCUCAUGGCCGUGUGCUACUUCCACUUAAUCUCCAGCUUGGGGCAAAGGUGUCCUUUGUUUGCGAUGAAGGGUUCCGAUUAAAAGGCAGGUCUGCUAGUCAUUGUGUCUUGGCUGGAAUGAAAGCCCUUUGGAAUAGCAGUGUUCCAGUGUGUGAACAAAUCUUUUGUCCAAAUCCUCCAGCUAUCCUUAAUGGGAGACACACAGGAACUCCCUUUGGAGAUAUUCCCUAUGGAAAAGAAAUAUCUUACGCAUGCGACACCCACCCAGACAGAGGGAUGACCUUCAACCUCAUUGGGGAGAGCUCCAUCCGCUGCACAAGUGACCCUCAAGGGAAUGGGGUUUGGAGCAGCCCUGCCCCUCGCUGUGAACUUUCUGUUCCUGCUGCCUGCCCACAUCCACCCAAGAUCCAAAACGGGCAUUACAUUGGAGGACACGUAUCUCUAUAUCUUCCUGGGAUGACAAUCAGCUACAUUUGUGACCCCGGCUACCUGUUAGUGGGAAAGGGCUUCAUUUUCUGUACAGACCAGGGAAUCUGGAGCCAAUUGGAUCAUUAUUGCAAAGAAGUAAAUUGUAGCUUCCCACUGUUUAUGAAUGGAAUCUCGAAGGAGUUAGAAAUGAAAAAAGUAUAUCACUAUGGAGAUUAUGUGACUUUGAAGUGUGAAGAUGGGUAUACUCUGGAAGGCAGUCCCUGGAGCCAGUGCCAGGCGGAUGACAGAUGGGACCCUCCUCUGGCCAAAUGUACCUCUCGUACACAUGAUGCUCUCAUAGUUGGCACUUUAUCUGGUACGAUCUUCUUUAUUUUACUCAUCAUUUUCCUCUCUUGGAUAAUUCUAAAGCACAGAAAAGGCAAUAAUGCACAUGAAAACCCUAAAGAAGUGGCUAUCCAUUUACAUUCUCAAGGAGGCAGCAGCGUUCAUCCCCGAACUCUGCAAACAAAUGAAGAAAAUAGCAGGGUCCUUCCUUGACAAAGUACUAUACAGCUGAAGAACAUCUCGAAUACAAUUUUGGUGGGAAAGGAGCCAAUUGAUUUCAACAGAAUCAGAUCUGAGCUUCAUAAAGUCUUUGAAGUGACUUCACAGAGACGCAGACAUGUGCACUUGAAGAUGCUGCCCCUUCCCUGGUACCUAGCAAAGCUCCUGCCUCUUUGUGUGCGUCACUGUGAAACCCCCACCCUUCUGCCUCGUGCUAAACGCACACAGUAUCUAGUCAGGGGAAAAGACUGCAUUUAGGAGAUAGAAAAUAGUUUGGAUUACUUAAAGGAAUAAGGUGUUGCCUGGAAUUUCUGGUUUGUAAGGUGGUCACUGUUCUUUUUUAAAAUAUUUGUAAUAUGGAAUGGGCUCAGUAAGAAGAGCUUGGAAAAUGCAGAAAGUUAUGAAAAAUAAGUCACUUAUAAUUAUGCUACCUACUGAUAACCACUCCUAAUAUUUUGAUUCAUUUUCUGCCUAUCUUCUUUCACAUAUGUGUUUUUUUACAUACGUACUUUUCCCCCUUAGUUUGUUUCCUUUUAUUUUAUAGAGCAGAACCCUAGUCUUUUAAACAGUUUAGAGUGAAAUAUAUGCUAUAUCAGUUUUUACUUUCUCUAGGGAGAAAAAUUAAUUUACUAGAAAGGCAUGAAAUGAUCAUGGGAAGAGUGGUUAAGACUACUGAAGAGAAAUAUUUGGAAAAUAAGAUUUCGAUAUCUUCUUUUUUUUUGAGAUGGAGUCUGGCUCUGUCUCCCAGGCUGGAGUGCAGUGGCGUAAUCUCGGCUCACUGCAAGCUCCGCCUCCCGGGUUGACACCAUUUUCCUGCCUCAGCCUCCUGAGUAGUUGGGAUUACCAGUAGAUGGGACUACAGGCACCUGCCAACACGCCCGGCUAAUUUUUUUGUAUUUUUAGUAGAGACGGGGUUUCACCAUGUUAGCCAGGAUGGUCUGGAUCUCCUGACCUCGUGAUCCACCUGCCUCGGCCUCCCAAAGUGCUGCGAUUACAGGCAUGAGCCACCGCGCCUGGCCGCUUUCGAUAUUUUCUAAACUUUAAUUCAAAAGCACUUUGUGCUGUGUUCUAUAUAAAAAACAUAAUAAAAAUUGAAAUGAAAGAAUAAUUGUUAUUAUAAAAGUACUAGCUUACUUUUGUAUGGAUUCAGAAUAUACUAAAUUAACUUUUUAAAACACAACUUUUAAAAAAUGUAUCAAAAUAAUAAACGUGUUCUGAUAUUUUUAAAAUAAGUGACCUUGUGUUCUUUAACCAGUCCACAUCUUUAGAGAACAAAAAUGUGUUAUGAUAUUAUGGGCCAUGCUAAUGACCUCUAGAAAACAUCAGAAUAUUUCUGGAUAUUUAAUAAUAGCUUUAUAUAUGACUAAUGCUCAUUUCUAUGUAAUUCUGUUUAAUAGUUGCUUUAAAGGUGAAUUUUGCCACAUUUACUUUGACAGCAGUAUAAGGAGUGAGAUAGACAUGAACCUGAAUUUCAAUUUAAAAUCAUGGAAGAGAGGGAAAAAAAACCAGCUUAAGAAAAAUCAACUGAUAAACUGCAAGAAAAAAAUGCAACUUACAUCACAAAAGCUAAUUGCUUUAUUAUUUAGAGAGUACUUAAAAAUUAAAGACCAAACUUCUCUCCACCCAACAAAAAUGGGCAAAGGACAUACAGCUAGGUCACCAAGAAAGAAGGGCAAAUAGGUGGUGAGUAUAUGUAAAGAUACUUGAUAGGACUUUUGCUUAGUUGAAUCUUUAGCAAAUCUCUUUUAUUUCUUGGGAUUUUGAAGAAGUAAUUUUUAAAGGAGGACUAGAAACUAAGUGAUUGGGAAUUGGCCUUUUUAGAAUUAAAAUUUCCCAUUACAAGAAAAAAAAAUCCUGUGUUCUUUUUUUUUUCCAGAAUGGAGUAGGUCAGUGAGCAAUGUGAUUAAUAAAUAUUUCAAUGUCUGUGACUUUUGAUUUAUUUUGGAGACAGGGUCUUGCUCUGUUACCCAGGCUGGAGUGCAGUGGUGCUAUCUAGGCUUACUGCAACCUCACCUGUCACUUUUUAAUUGCAAGAAAGCUGAAAGGUUUUUUUCUAUUAUAUCAGUUAUAAUGAUAAAUACUGUAUAUACUAACUAUGAGUAAAAUACUAUAUUGCCUAACUUGUAUUAUUAAGCAAUUCUGCUAACCUGUGACCUUACAUUUUCAUCUGAAAAGCAGGGGCUGGACACCAAUUGCCCUAUGAAGCUAUUGCUAGUCCUAACAUUCUUUGUUUUGUUUGCUUUUUUGGCACACUUAAGUGUGUACUAUGAAGUUUAUGAUGCUUUAAUGAAAUUUUCUGUCUCUACCAUUGUAAUGAGAAAGGAAUAAAAUACUUUAUUUUGCAAAUCUA